ACUCCCGAGCCCCGAGAGCUCCGCGCACCUGGGCGCCAUCCGCCCUGGCUCCGCUGCACGAGCUCCACGCCCGUACCCCGGCGUCACGCUCAGCCCGCGGUGCUCGCACACCUGAGACUCAUCUCGCUUCGACCCCGCCGCCGCCGCCGCCCGGCAUCCUGAGCACGGAGACAGUCUCCAGCUGCCGUUCAUGCUUCCUCCCCAGCCUUCCGCAGCCCACCAGGGAAGGGGCGGUAGGAGUGGCCUUUUACCAAAGGUCAGAUUCUUUCACCGCCUCUGCCAGACCCCCUUGUCCCCCACCCCCGCAUAGAUCUCCAGGGGGCUCAGAAAACUCUGGCCGGUGGCUCACGCCUGUAGUCCCAACGCUUUGGGAGGCCAAGGCGGGAGGAUCGCUUGAGGCCAGGAGUUCCAGACCAGCCCAGGCAACAAAAGAUACCACAUCUCUACAAAAAAUAAAUUAGCCGGGCCCUGCACGCCUGUAGUCCCAGCUACUGGGGAGGCCGAGGCCGGAGGAUCGCUUGAACCCAGGAGUUCCAGGCUGCAGUGAGCUAUAAUUGUGCCACUGCACUAGAGUCUGGGUGACAGAGACACUGUCUCAAAAAAAACCAACAAAACCCUUAGCUCUUUCACUAGCCGGGCUGGCCUCUUCCUACUGUAAACCUGCUGGGCCCCCGUCUCCCUUCUUUCUCCCCUCUCUCCUGCCCUGGAGCUGCCUGACUCUGCCCACGGCCUGCAGAGACCCCAGGUCUUCACGCAAGGUGCCAUUCCUCACUCAGUUCUUGCUCAAACGUCCCUCCAUCAAGGAGGGCUUUUUAGCUACCCUUGGCUAUGGGAUCCGUCCUCCGCGUCAGCCAAUUCUCUGCAUUAGACUGUAACUUCUCAACAUACCUGGUUCCUAUGCGUUUUGUGCUCCCCUCUGAGAGGGCAGCGACCCUGUCUUGCUUGCCACUGCAUCCCUAGCACCUAGCAGUUGCUUUUCUGGUGACGGCGGCUGUGGCAGUGGCCAAUGCGGCAGACUGGUCAGAAGUGAAGGGACAGGAUGACUUGGCAGUGGAGGUCAAGGGGAGGGGACUGGGGCAGAGGGAGACACCAGAGGGACAAAAAUGAGAAACUGAAGACAGGCUUUGCUACGUGGAGCUCGGGCAGGCCACACUGGUGGAUUCUGUCUCCUCAUCCUUCUUUUCAGGUCCCUGGGAGAAAUCAGCACUUAGAACGUGGUGGGAAGGCGGGGCGGGGUGCCUCGGAAGCCAUCCCUGAUACAAGUCCCCAGCUUUCCUGCUUCCCCUCUUGUGGUGUGUGGCUUUGUCUCCCUCCCUCCCUCCUGGAAGCCCCGACCUCUGAGGCAGGUGUAAAGGGUGUGUGCUUUGGUGGCCACGGCCACCCUGUGGUGCUGGUUCUCCUCCGAGGGAAGCAGUGCACUCCUGGUCAUCUUGGAGACGCCCAACACAGGACCCCACAGGCACCAAGCUUUUUUUGGGAAAUGGUUUCACUUCCCACUUGAAAAGCCCUGAAUGUCAGUUCCACACUUAGUGAAUUUGAUCCAAGCUAAACUGAGUCUGUGCCUAAAACUCAUCAGGUGCUCGAGUUUCCUGGAAGAAUGGCUGGGAACGUUUAUGGUGUCAGCUGUAAAGUGGCUGCAAGUCCUUUUGGGAAAAACAGACCCAGGAGUCCUCAGAUGAUGGCAGAGGAGGGCAAGGGCUGGCAAAGCAGCUGUGCUUAGCCCAUCCUCAGGGGAGGGAGGACUCUGGAAAGAGCCUGAGGAUACGCUGAGAAUAAAAAGUCCAGAGGCCAGCAGGGACUUAGCGGCUGGGGUGCAGGUUAACUCCUGCCCAACUCUUGGGGACAGGGACCCGGGGCUGGGCCCUGCUCAGGUGGCUCUCUCCUUGCAGGGACCGGCGAUGCUCUGCAGGCUGUGCUGGCUGGUCUCGUACAGCUUGGCUGUGCUGUUGCUCGGCUGCCUGCUCUUCCUGAGGAAGGCGGCCAAGCCCGCAGGAGACCCCACGGCCCACCAGCCUUUCUGGGCUCCCCCAACACCCCGUCACAGCCGGUGUCCACCCAACCACACAGUGUCUAGCGCCUCUCUGUCCCUGCCUAGCCGUCACCGUCUCUUCUUGACCUAUCGUCACUGCCGAAAUUUCUCUAUCUUGCUGGAGCCUUCAGGCUGUUCCAAGGAUACCUUCUUGCUCCUGGCCAUCAAGUCACAGCCUGGUCACGUGGAGCGACGUGCGGCUAUCCGCAGCACGUGGGGCAGGGUGGGGGGAUGGGCUAGGGGCCGGCAGCUGAAGCUGGUGUUCCUCCUAGGGGUGGCAGGAUCCGCUCCCCCAGCCCAGCUGCUGGCCUAUGAGAGUAGGGAGUUUGAUGACAUCCUCCAGUGGGACUUCACUGAGGACUUCUUCAACCUGACGCUCAAGGAGCUGCACCUGCAGCGCUGGGUGGUGGCUGCCUGCCCCCAGGCCCAUUUCAUGCUAAAGGGAGAUGACGAUGUCUUUGUCCACGUCCCCAACGUGUUAGAGUUCCUGGAUGGCUGGGACCCAGCCCAGGACCUCCUGGUGGGAGAUGUCAUCCGCCAAGCCCUGCCCAACAGGAACACUAAGGUCAAAUACUUCAUCCCACCCUCAAUGUACAGGGCCACCCACUACCCACCCUAUGCUGGUGGGGGAGGAUAUGUCAUGUCCAGAGCCACAGUGCGGCGCCUCCAGGCUAUCAUGGAAGAUGCUGAACUCUUCCCCAUUGAUGAUGUCUUUGUGGGUAUGUGCCUGAGGCGGCUGGGGCUGAGCCCUAUGCACCAUGCUGGCUUCAAGACAUUUGGAAUCCGGCGGCCCCUGGACCCCUUAGACCCCUGCCUGUAUAGGGGGCUCCUGCUGGUUCACCGCCUCAGCCCCCUCGAGAUGUGGACCAUGUGGGCACUGGUGACAGAUGAGGGGCUCAAGUGUGCAGCUGGCCCCAUACCCCAGCGCUGAAGGGUGGGUUGGGCAACAGCCUGAGAGUGGACUCAGUGUUGAUUCUCUAUCGUGAUGCGAAAUUGAUGCCUGCUGCUCUACAGAAAAUGCCAACUUGGUUUUUUAACUCCUCUCACCCUGUUAGCUCUGAUUAAAAACACUGCAACCCA